GCUCCUCUCCCCGCGCCGCCCCGCCCUCCGCCGCAGCCCGCGCCGGGGGUGGGGGCCGCCGAGCGCCAGCCCCCCGGCCGGCCGAUUCCCCCCCCGCGCCCCCUCCCCGCGCCUCCCUCCCCGCCCUCGCCGCGCCGCCGUCCUCGCCUCCCUCUGCCUCUCCUUCCCCCAUUCUCCCGGAUUAAUUAAGGAGGCAGCGGCAGGAGGCUGAGUCCUGGCCGCGGGCCGGGGCCGGGGCGCCGCUGGCAGGAGCGCUUGGGGAUCCUCCAAGGCGACCAUGGCCUUGCUGGGUAAGCGCUGUGACGUCCCCACCAACGGCUGCGGACCCGACCGCUGGAACUCCGCGUUCACCCGCAAAGACGAGAUCAUCACCAGCCUCGUGUCUGCCUUAGACUCCAUGUGCUCAGCGCUGUCCAAACUGAACGCCGAGGUGGCCUGUGUCGCCGUGCACGAUGAGAGCGCCUUUGUGGUGGGCACAGAGAAGGGGAGAAUGUUCCUGAAUGCCCGGAAGGAGCUACAGUCAGACUUCCUCAGGUUCUGCCUCUCCGCAGCUCAGCACAGGGCAGCGACAUCCCAGCUCGAAGGCCGGGUGGUGAGACGGGUGCUCACUGUGGCCUCGCGUGCUCUGUGUCCCACAGGAGGGCCCCCGUGGAAGGAUCCGGAGGCAGAGCACCCCAAGAAGGUGCAGCGGGGCGAGGGUGGAGGCCGUAGCCUCCCUCGGUCCUCCCUGGAACAUGGCUCAGAUGUGUACCUUCUGCGGAAGAUGGUAGAGGAGGUGUUUGAUGUUCUUUAUAGCGAGGCCCUGGGAAGGGCCAGUGUGGUGCCACUGCCCUAUGAGAGGCUGCUCAGGGAGCCAGGGCUGCUGGCCGUGCAGGGGCUGCCCGAAGGCCUGGCCUUCCGAAGGCCAGCCGAGUAUGACCCCAAGGCCCUCAUGGCCAUCCUGGAACACAGCCACCGCAUCCGCUUCAAGCUCAAGAGGCCACUUGAGGAUGGCGGGCGGGACUCGAAGGCCCUGGUGGAGCUGAACGGUGUCUCCCUGAUUCCCAAGGGGUCACGGGACUGUGGCCUGCAUGGCCAGGCCCCCAAGGUGCCACCCCAGGACCUGCCCCCAACCGCCACCUCCUCCUCCAUGGCCAGCUUCCUGUACAGCACGGCGCUCCCCAACCACGCCAUCCGAGAGCUCAAGCAGGAAGCACCUUCCUGCCCCCUUGCCCCCAGCGACCUGGGCCUGAGUCGGCCCAUGCCAGAGCCCAAGGCCACCGGUGCCCAAGACUUCUCCGACUGUUGUGGACAGAAGCCCACUGGGCCUGGUGGGCCUCUCAUCCAGAACGUCCAUGCCUCCAAGCGCAUUCUCUUCUCCAUCGUCCAUGACAAGUCAGAGAAGUGGGACGCCUUCAUAAAGGAAACCGAGGACAUCAACACGCUCCGGGAGUGUGUGCAGAUCCUGUUUAACAGCAGAUAUGCGGAAGCCCUGGGCCUGGACCACAUGGUCCCCGUGCCCUACCGGAAGAUUGCCUGUGACCCGGAGGCUGUGGAGAUCGUGGGCAUCCCGGACAAGAUCCCCUUCAAGCGCCCCUGCACUUAUGGAGUCCCCAAGCUGAAGCGGAUCCUGGAGGAGCGCCAUAGUAUCCACUUCAUCAUUAAGAGGAUGUUUGAUGAGCGAAUUUUCACAGGGAACAAGUUUACCAAAGACACCACGAAGCUGGAGCCAGCCAGCCCGCCAGAGGACACCUCUGCAGAGGUCUCUAGGGCCACCGUCCUUGACCUUGCUGGGAAUGCUCGGUCAGACAAGGGCAGCAUGUCUGAAGACUGUGGGCCAGGAACCUCCGGGGAGCUGGGCGGGCUGAGGCCGAUCAAAAUUGAGCCAGAGGAUCUGGACAUCAUUCAGGUCACCGUCCCAGACCCCUCGCCAACCUCUGAGGAAAUGACAGACUCGAUGCCUGGGCACCUGCCAUCGGAGGAUUCUGGUUAUGGGAUGGAGAUGCUGACAGACAAAGGUCUGAGUGAGGACGCGCGGCCCGAGGAGAGGCCCGUGGAGGACAGCCACGGUGACGUGAUCCGGCCCCUGCGGAAGCAGGUGGAGCUGCUCUUCAACACACGAUACGCCAAGGCCAUUGGCAUCUCGGAGCCCGUCAAGGUGCCGUACUCCAAGUUUCUGAUGCACCCGGAGGAGCUGUUUGUGGUGGGACUGCCUGAAGGCAUCUCCCUCCGCAGGCCCAACUGCUUCGGGAUCGCCAAGCUCCGGAAGAUUCUGGAGGCCAGCAACAGCAUCCAGUUUGUCAUCAAGAGGCCCGAGCUGCUCACUGAGGGAGUCAAAGAGCCCAUCAUGGAUAGUCAAGGAACUGCCUCCUCACUUGGCUUCUCUCCCCCUGCCCUGCCCCCAGAGAGGGAUUCCGGGGACCCUCUGGUGGACGAGAGCCUGAAGAGACAGGGCUUUCAAGAAAAUUAUGACGCGAGGCUCUCACGGAUCGACAUCGCCAACACACUAAGGGAGCAGGUCCAGGACCUUUUCAAUAAGAAAUACGGGGAAGCCUUGGGCAUCAAGUACCCGGUCCAGGUCCCCUACAAGCGGAUCAAGAGUAACCCCGGCUCCGUGAUCAUCGAGGGGCUGCCCCCAGGAAUCCCGUUCCGAAAGCCCUGUACCUUCGGCUCCCAGAACCUGGAGAGGAUUCUUGCUGUGGCUGACAAGAUCAAGUUCACAGUCACCAGGCCUUUCCAAGGACUCAUCCCAAAGCCUGAUGAAGAUGACGCCAACAGACUCGGGGAGAAGGUGAUCCUGCGGGAGCAGGUGAAGGAACUCUUCAACGAGAAAUACGGUGAGGCCCUGGGCCUGAACCGGCCGGUGCUGGUCCCUUAUAAACUAAUCCGGGACAGCCCAGACGCCGUGGAGGUCACGGGUCUGCCUGAUGACAUCCCCUUCCGGAACCCCAACACGUACGACAUCCACCGGCUGGAGAAGAUCCUGAAGGCCCGAGAGCAUGUCCGCAUGGUCAUCAUUAACCAGCUCCAACCCUUUGCAGAAAUCUGCAAUGAUGCCAAGGUGCCAGCCAAAGACAGCAGCAUUCCCAAGCGCAAGAGAAAGCGGGUCUCGGAAGGAAAUUCCGUCUCCUCUUCCUCCUCGUCUUCCUCUUCCUCGUCCUCUAACCCGGAUUCAGUGGCAUCGGCCAACCAGAUCUCACUCGUGGUAAAGUUGCACCGAUUUGGACUCCGGCACUCAUCUCUGUGGCCCUCACCCCUCUGUCUGGCAGGGCCGUCUACUCUGGGAUGUGGGCCCAGGGGACGGGGAGGCACUGGGCUUUGAGUGGGGACCUUCCGGCCUCGGGGGUUAUAGAUGCAUCCACCUGUCUCACCCAAGAGGUAGCCCAUCCUUCUCGUGGGGUACUCACAGGCACUCAGGCAGGAAUUCACAUCCUCGCUGGGCAGAUGGGCCGGCUGAGGUCCACCUGCCCACACCCUUCAGCCGCACCAGAGCUGGAGACAUGAAAAGACAUGGCUGGCGGGUGCAGUGGCUCACGCCUGUAAUCCCAGCACUUUGGCAGGUCAAGUCGGGUGGAUCACCUGAGGUCAGGAGUUUGAGACCAGGCUGACCAACACGGGGAAACCCCAUCUCUACUAAAAAUACAAAAUUAGCCGGGCAAAGUGGGGCAUAGUGGCUCAUGCCUGUAAUCCCAGCUACUUGGAAGGCUGAGAUAGGAGAAUCGCUUGAACCUGGGAGGCAGAGGUUGCAAUGAGCCGAGGUCGCGCCAUUGCACUGCAGCCUGGGCAACAAGAGUGAAACACUGUCUCAGAAAAAAAAAUUAGCCAGGCAUGGUGGCACGUGCCUGUGGUCGCAGCUACUUGGGAGGCUGGGGCAGGAGGAUCAUUUGAGCCCAAGGGGAUUGAGGCUGCAGUGAGCCAAGAUCGUCCCAUUGCACUCCAGCCUGGGCAAGAGAACGAGACUCCAUCUCAAAAAUAAAUAAAUAGGCUGGGUGUGGUGGCUCACGCCUGUAAUCCUAGCACUUUGGGAGGCCGAGGCAGGCGGAUCACUUGAGGCUCAGGAGUUCAAGACCAGCCUGGCCAACAUGGCAAAACCCCGUCUCUACUAAAAAUAGAAAAAUUAGCCGGGCAUGGUGGCGGGCGCCUAUAAUCCCAGCUACUCGGGAGGCUGAGGCAGGAGACUCGCUUGAACCCGCGGGGCCAAGGUUGCAGUGAGCCGAGAUUGCAUCACUGCACUCCAGCCUGGGCAGAAGAGUGAAACUCCAUCUCAAAAAAAUAAAAAAUAUAAAUAAAUAGCCUCUGAGAAAGCUCUUCCAAAAGCA